AGAGCCUUCCCUGAUCUGCCUCCAGCACUGCCCAUCCUUGCCCCUUUCCACUGUCCUUGGAGCUUCCUGGGCCCUUCCCUGGGCCUCAGGAUCCCACCCUCCAUCCCGUCUGCCCUGCAGGAUGCCGCAGCUGAGCCUGUCCUGGCUGGGCCUCGGGCCCGUGGCAGCAUCCCCGUGGCUGCUUCUGCUGCUGGUUGGAGGCUCCUGGCUCCUGGCCCGCGUCCUGGCCUGGACCUACACCUUCUAUGACAACUGCCGCCGCCUCCAGUGUUUUCCUCAACCCCCGAAACAGAACUGGUUUUGGGGACACCAGGGCCUGGUCACUCCCACGGAAGAGGGCAUGAAGACAUUGACCCAGCUGGUGACCACAUAUCCCCAGGGCUUUAAGUUGUGGCUGGGUCCUACCUUCCCCCUCCUCAUUUUAUGCCACCCUGACAUUAUCCGGCCUAUCACCAGUGCCUCAGCUGCUGUCGCACCCAAGGAUAUGAUUUUCUAUGGCUUCCUGAAGCCCUGGCUGGGGGAUGGGCUCCUGCUGAGUGGUGGUGACAAGUGGAGCCGCCACCGUCGGAUGUUGACGCCUGCCUUCCAUUUCAACAUCUUGAAGCCUUAUAUGAAGAUUUUCAACAAGAGUGUGAACAUCAUGCACGACAAGUGGCAGCGCCUGGCCUCAGAGGGCAGCGCCAGACUGGACAUGUUUGAACACAUCAGCCUCAUGACCUUGGACAGUCUGCAGAAAUGUGUCUUCAGCUUUGAAAGCAAUUGUCAGGAGAAGCCCAGUGAAUAUAUUGCCGCCAUCUUGGAGCUCAGUGCCUUUGUAGAAAAGAGAAACCAGCAGAUUCUCUUGCACACGGACUUCCUGUAUUAUCUCACUCCUGAUGGGCAGCGCUUCCGCAGGGCCUGCCACCUGGUGCACGACUUCACAGAUGCCGUCAUCCAGGAGCGGCGCUGCACCCUCCCCACUCAGGGUAUUGAUGAUUUCCUCAAGAACAAGGCAAAGUCCAAGACUUUAGACUUCAUUGAUGUGCUUCUGCUGAGCAAGGAUGAAGAUGGGAAGGAAUUGUCUGAUGAGGACAUAAGAGCAGAAGCUGACACCUUCAUGUUUGAGGGCCAUGACACUACAGCCAGUGGUCUCUCCUGGGUCCUAUACCACCUUGCAAAGCACCCAGAAUACCAGGAACAGUGCCGGCAAGAAGUGCAAGAGCUUCUGAAGGACCGUGAACCUAUAGAGAUUGAAUGGGACGACCUGGCCCAGCUGCCCUUCCUGACCAUGUGCAUUAAGGAGAGCCUGCGGUUGCAUCCCCCAGUCCCGGUCAUCUCCCGAUGUUGCACGCAGGACUUUGUGCUCCCAGACGGCCGCGUCAUCCCCAAAGGCAUUGUCUGCCUCAUCAAUAUUAUCGGGAUCCAUUACAACCCAACUGUGUGGCCAGACCCUGAGGUCUACGACCCCUUCCGUUUCGACCAAGAGAACAUCAAGGAGAGGUCACCUCUGGCUUUUAUUCCCUUCUCGGCAGGGCCCAGAAACUGCAUCGGGCAGGCGUUCGCCAUGGCUGAGAUGAAGGUGGUCCUGGCGCUCACCCUGCUGCACUUCCGCAUCCUGCCGACCCACACUGAACCCCGCAGGAAACCCGAGCUGAUAUUGCGCGCAGAGGGUGGACUUUGGCUGCGGGUGGAGCCCCUGGGUGCGAACUCACAGUGACUGUCCUACCCACCCACCCACCUCUGUAGAGUCCCAGAAACAAAACUAUGCUGACACCUCUGCUUGAGCCUCGUUGACAGCCAGCAUGGGGCUCCUGGGGACUGGUGGGAUCUAAGAAAGGGAGGUGAGUGGGUGGAGGCAGGGUGACGUCUCUGAACCCAAAACCCUGACGGCCUCUCUGGCUGAGCACAGGGCAUCUAGGCCCUUAGUGGGUUCUCCCAGAGCCCAAGUAAAAACUUUAUCCUGUGGGCAGUAGGGAGCCCUGGGAGGUGUUUGAGCAGGAGAGGGAACAGGAUUAAGAAUGGGUUUAAGGAGCAAGACUGAGACUCUGAUUCAGCGAGAAACAACCAUAGGGGCAGAUCCCUUCAUCUGUCCUGGGAAUGUCCUCCCAAGACUGGAGUCCUCAGCUCAGAACAAAGGGAAAGGGGUGCAGCUUCCACCCUGGCAGGCUCUCAGAAAUUUUUAGUUCCUUUUUCCACCAACUUCCCACCCCUGUUUCUCCCCCUCCCAGUGCGUUCUCUCUGUGACUCUCUUCCCUUACUUUCAGAGGCAUAGGAUCUGGAGCCAGACUGCUUGGGCUCAAGUCCUGGCUCUGCUGCGUGACUUGAGCAAGUUAAUUCCUCUCUCUGUGCCUCGGUUCCCUCAACCAUAUAAUGGAGACAACAGCAUUACCUAUAUCAGGGUUUUCCUGAGGUCUCAAUAUAAGGGACUCAGAGCUGUGCCUGGCACACAAUGAAUGCUAAAUAUAUGGAGCCAUUAUUAUUUCCUGUCUCAGAAAGUCUGGCUGUUAAAGAAUGUUGUCUUUCAAGAUCGUUAUUUCUACCACGACUUUAAAGGCUGUGUUUUGGAACUCAAAGGCAAAAAUUCUAAUAUCUGUGCUCCUUGAACAACCUCUUCUCCUAGAGGGCUGUGCAUAUAAGAUAUGUAUAUAUAUAUAUAUAUUAUAUAUAUAUAUAUAUACACACACACACACACACACACACACAUAUAUACAUAUACACACACACACACACACACACACACACACACACACAUAUAUAUAUAUAUAUAUUUUUUUUUUUUUCCUGAGGAUGGUGAAGGUACCUGACUGUGUGAGGUGGUAGGAGAAUGAGAGAAACCUCAGUCAGUGUCUCAAAAUAAAAUCCUGCUACAAACAUUGAUCUCUUUUCAUAGCCUAAGGGAUGUUGCAUCGCUAAACCCUGUUGACUUCUCUAAUCUCUUCUGUAGCUGAUCUCCUUCCCUUGCUACACUCGGUUACUCUGGCCUUGAUUCUGAUCUCCAAAUACAUUAUAUUUUUUAUUUGGGACCAUCGUAUUGCCUUUGCACCUUUAUCAAAUAUAAGUUGCCUAUAUUUA